AUCCUCUGGGUCGGCACUGUUGGAGAACGCUCAGGGUCUGGUGCUCUCGUGCCUGCCCCUUCCAGGCAGCCGGCUCUGAUUGCACAAGGCAGACCUGUGACUCCUCCAUCCAGCUAUGCCCCUGCUGCCCAGCACCGUGGGCCUGGCAGGCCUGCUCUUCUGGGCUGGCCAGGCAGUGAACGCCUUGAUAAUGCCUAAUGCUACCCCAGCCCCGGCCCAGCCCGAGAGCACGGCUAUGCGGCUCCUGAGUGGCCUGGAGGUGCCCAGGUACCGCCGGAAGCGCCACAUCUCUGUGAGAGACAUGAAUGCCUUACUGGAUUAUCACAACCACAUCCGGGCCAGUGUGUACCCACCUGCCGCCAACAUGGAAUACAUGGUCUGGGACAAGCGGCUGGCCAGGGCUGCCGAAGCCUGGGCCACCCAGUGCAUCUGGGCACAUGGGCCUUCACAGCUGAUGAGAUACGUGGGCCAGAACCUCUCCAUCCAUUCUGGCCAGUACCGGUCCGUAGUGGAUCUCAUGAAGUCCUGGUCUGAGGAGAAGUGGCAUUACUUGUUUCCGGCCCCAAGGGACUGUAACCCACACUGCCCCUGGCGCUGCGAUGGCCCCACCUGCUCCCAUUAUACCCAGAUGGUGUGGGCAUCCUCCAAUCGGCUGGGCUGUGCCAUCCACACCUGUAGUAGCAUCAGUGUCUGGGGCAACACCUGGCAUCGGGCGGCAUACCUGGUCUGCAACUAUGCCAUUAAGGGCAACUGGAUUGGCGAGUCCCCGUACAAGAUGGGAAAGCCGUGCUCCUCCUGUCCCCCCAGUUAUCAAGGCAGCUGCAAUAGCAACAUGUGCUUCAAGGGGCUGAAAUCCAACAAGUUCACGUGGUUCUGAAUUUUCUCUGGGCUUUGGUGCGCCUCCAGCUGGGCCUGACCCUCCAUGUCCUGCCCUCAAAAAACUGGGUGGAGAAAUAAUUGUUUCUUUAAAGGAUAUGAGUUAGAAUCACCCCCUGUUGAAUUUUCCCUCCUAGAUCCCCUUCUUAAAUGUCCAACAUGGGUCAAAAGAAAAUGACCUCCUUGCCUUCCUUCUUUCCUAGUUGCAUCUUUCUUUUCUUGGGCCUCUGGGAAAGAGCCCUGCAUCUUUCAUUAAUUCGGUUCUCAGAGAACCAAGGCUGGAAGGCAUAGAACUGGCACCUUGGGACCAGGCAUAAUGGCUCACACCUAUAAUCCCAGUAUUUUGGGAGGCUGAGGUGGGAGAAUCACUUGAGUCCUGGAGUUGGAGAACAGCCUGGAAAGCCUGGCGAUACCCCAUCUCUAUUUAGAAACAAACAAACAAACAAA